GACUCCCUUCUCGUCUCGAGGCCUGUGGCGUCUGGGUCCGUUGGGGCAGAACCAUGGAGGAAAAGCCUUCGAAAGUGUCGCUCAAGUCUUCCGACCGCCAAGGCUCGGACGAGGAGAGCGUGCAUAGCGACACUCGGGACCUGUGGACCACGACCACGCUGUCCCAGGCACAGCUGAACAUGCCGCUGUCCGAGGUCUGCGAGGGCUUCGACGAGGAGGGCCGCAACAUUAGCAAGACCCGCGGGUGGCACAGCCCGGGGCGGGGCUCGUUGGACGAGGGGUACAAGGCCAGCCACAAGCCGGAGGAACUGGACGAGCACGCGCUGGUGGAGCUGGAGUUGCACCGCGGCAGCUCCAUGGAAAUCAAUCUGGGGGAGAAGGACACUGCAUCCCAGAUCGAGGCCGAAAAGUCUUCCUCAAUGUCAUCACUCAAUAUUGCGAAGCACAUGCCCCAUCGAGCCUACUGGGCAGAGCAGCAGAGCAGGCUGCCACUGCCCCUGAUGGAACUCAUGGAGAAUGAAGCUCUGGAAAUCCUCACCAAAGCCCUCCGGAGCUACCAGUUAGGGAUCGGCAGGGACCACUUCCUGACUAAGGAGCUGCAGCGAUACAUCGAAGGGCUCAAGAAGCGCCGGAGCAAGAGGCUGUACGUGAAUUAAAAACGCCACCUUGGGCUCGAGCAGCGACCCGAACCAGCCCCGUGCCAGCCCGGUCCCCAGACCCAAGCCUGACCCCAUCCGAGUGGAAUUUGAGUCCUAAAGAAAUAAAAGAGUCGAUGCAUGG